CUCUCCUUGUUUUGCUUUCGAUCUGGACUGUUCUCAGGCAAGCCGGGGAGUAACUUUUAGUUUUGCUCCUGCGAUUAUUCAACUGACGGGCUUUCAUUUCCAUUUCACAUACCCUAGCAACACUUAUACCUUGCGGAAUUGUAUUGGUAGCGUGAAAAAAGCACACUGAGAGGGCACCAUGCCGGUGGAAAGGAUGCGCAUGCGCCCGUGGCUGGAGGAGCAGAUAAACUCCAACACGAUCCCGGGGCUCAAGUGGCUUAACAAGGAAAAGAAGAUUUUUCAGAUCCCCUGGAUGCAUGCGGCUAGACAUGGGUGGGAUGUGGAAAAAGAUGCACCACUCUUUAGAAACUGGGCAAUCCAUACAGGAAAGCAUCAACCAGGAGUAGAUAAACCUGAUCCCAAAACAUGGAAGGCGAAUUUCAGAUGCGCCAUGAAUUCCUUGCCUGAUAUUGAAGAAGUCAAGGAUAAAAGCAUAAAGAAAGGAAAUAAUGCCUUCAGGGUCUACCGAAUGCUGCCCCUAUCAGAACGGCCUUCUAAGAAAGGAAAGAAACCAAAGACAGAAAAAGAAGACAAAGUUAAGCACAUCAAGCAAGAACCAGUUGAGUCAUCUCUGGGGCUUAGUAAUGGAGUAAGUGAUCUUUCUCCUGAGUAUGCGGUCCUGACUUCAACUAUAAAAAAUGAAGUGGAUAGUACGGUGAACAUCAUAGUUGUAGGACAGUCCCAUCUGGACAGCAACAUUGAGAAUCAAGAGAUUGUCACCAAUCCGCCAGACAUUUGCCAAGUUGUAGAGGUGACCACUGAGAGCGACGAGCAGCCGGUCAGCAUGAGCGAGCUCUACCCUCUGCAGAUCUCCCCCGUGUCUUCCUAUGCAGAAAGCGAAACGACUGAUAGUGUGCCCAGCGAUGAAGAGAGUGCCGAGGGGCGGCCACACUGGCGGAAGAGGAAUAUUGAAGGCAAACAGUACCUCAGCAACAUGGGGACUCGAGGCUCCUACCUGCUGCCCGGCAUGGCGUCCUUCGUCACUUCCAACAAACCGGACCUCCAGGUCACCAUCAAAGAGGAGAGCAAUCCGGUGCCUUACAACAGCUCCUGGCCCCCUUUUCAAGACCUCCCCCUUUCUUCCUCCAUGACCCCAGCAUCCAGCAGCAGUCGGCCAGACCGGGAGACCCGGGCCAGCGUCAUCAAGAAAACAUCGGAUAUCACCCAGGCCCGCGUCAAGAGCUGUUAAGCCUCUGACUCUCCGCGGUGGUUGUUGGGGCUUCUUGGCUUUGUUUUGUUGUUUGUUUGUAUUUUAUUUUUUUCUCUCUGACACCUAUUUUAGACAAAUCUAAGGGAAAAAGCCUUGACAAUAGAACAUUGAUUGCUGUGUCCAACUCCAGUACUGGAGCUUCUCUUUAACUCAGGACUCCAGCCCAUUGGUAGACGUGUGUUUCUAGAGCCUGCUGGAUCUCCCAGGGCUACUCACUCAAGUUCAAGGACCAACAAGGGCAGUGGAGGUGCUGCAUUGCCUGCGGUCAAGGCCAGCAAGGUGGAGUGGAUGCCUCAGAACGGACGAGAUAAUGUGAACUAGCUGGAAUUUUUUAUUCUUGUGAAUAUGUACAUAGGCAGCACUAGCGACAUUGCAGUCUGCUUCUGCACCUUAUCUUAAAGCACUUACAGAUAGGCCUUCUUGUGAUCUUGCUCUAUCUCACAGCACACUCAGCACCCCCUUCUCUGCCCAUUCCCCAGCCUCUCUUCCUAUCCCAUCCCAUCCCAUCCCAUCCCAUCCCAUCCCAUCCCGCUCUUUUCCUACUUUUCCUUCCCUCAAAGCUUCCAUUCCACAUCCGGAGGAGAAGAAGGAAAUGAAUUUCUCUACAGAUGUCCCAUUUUCAGACUGCUUUAAAAAAAAUCCUUCUAAUCUGCUAUGCUUGAAUGCCACGCGGUACAAAGGAAAAAGUAUCAUGGAAAUAUUAUGCAAAUUCCCAGAUUUGAAGACAAAAAUACUCUAAUUCUAACCAGAGCAAGCUUUUUUAUUUUUUAUACAGGGGAAUAUUUUAUUCAAGGUAAAAUUCUAAAUAAAAUAUAAUUGUUUUUUAUCUUUUCUACAGCAAAUUUAUAAUUUUAAGAUUCCUUUUCUUGUUUAUCAGCAGUUGUUAUUACAUCCUUGUGGCACAUUUUUUUUUUUAAUUUUGUAAAGGUGAAAAAAGCUUUUAUGAGCUCAUGUAGCAAUCAGAUUUUCCUGUGGAUUGAUAAUAAAUGAAUAUGAUAUAUAGUUAAA